CUCACUGUGUGUGACUCUGGGCACGCUGCUUAAGCUCUCUGAGCCCUGGUGUCCUCAUUUACAACACAGGGAUGAUAACAGAACUCCGUUGGAGGGUGCUUGGCAGGGCUGAAUCGGAUGACUGGGCGAAAAGCCAGCGGUGGCACACCUUGCACUCUGCGUAAAGGGGCGCCUAUUAUCACCUUGGGGAAGAACUGGACAGAGCGCCUGGCGGCGGGUGAUUCAGUUGGGUGCUCUGGGGCCAGGUGCCACCGGCCAUUGUCCAGGCAGCUGUGUGCAAGCCAAAGAAGCAUGAGGACACUGGAAGACUCCUCGGGGACAGUCCUGCACCGCCUCAUCCAGGAGCAGCUGCGCUACGGCAACCUGACUGAGACGCGCACGCUGCUAGCCAUCCAGCAGCAGGCCCUGAGGGGUGGGGCUGGAACUGGGGGUACAGGGAGCCCCCAGGCCUCCCUGGAGAUCCUGGCCCCAGAGGACAGUCAGGUGCUGCAGCAGGCCACCAGGCAGGAGCCCCAGGGCCAGGAGCACCAGGGCGGUGAGAACCACCUGGCAGAGAACACCCUCUACCGGCUAUGCCCACAGCCCAGCAAGGGAGAGGAGCUGCCCACCUAUGAGGAGGCCAAAGCCCACUCGCAGUACUAUGCGGCCCAGCAGGCAGGGACCCGGCCACAUGCGGGGGACCGAGAUCCCCGUGGGGCCCCGGGAGGCAGUCGGAGGCAGGACGAGGCCCUGCGGGAGCUGAGGCAUGGGCACGUGCGCUCGUUGAGUGAACGGCUCCUUCAGUUGUCCCUGGAGAGGAACGGCGCCCGGGCCCCCAGCCACAUGAGCUCCUCCCACAGCUUCCCACAGCUGGCCCGCAACCAGCAGGGCCCCCCACUGAGGGGCCCCCCUGCUGAGGGCCCAGAGUCCCGAGGACCCCCACCUCAGUACCCUCAUGUUGUACUAGCUCAUGAGACCACCACUGCUGUCACUGACCCACGGUACCGUGCCCGCGGCAGCCCGCACUUCCAGCAUGCUGAAGUCAGGAUCCUGCAGGCCCAGGUGCCUCCUGUGUUCCUCCAACAGCAGCAGCAGUACCAGUACCUGCAGCAAUCUCAGGAGCACCCCCCUCCCCCACAUCCAGCUGCUCUCGGCCAUGGCCCCCUGAGCUCCCUCAGUCCACCUGCUGUGGAGGGGCCAGUGAGUGCCCAGGCCUCCUCAGCCACCUCGGGCAGUGCCCACCUGGCCCAGAUGGAGGCCGUGCUGAGGGAGAAUGCCAGGCUGCAGAGAGACAAUGAGCGGCUGCAGAGGGAGCUGGAGAGCUCUGCGGAGAAGGCUGGCCGCAUUGAGAAGCUGGAAAGCGAAAUCCAGCGGCUCUCUGAGGCCCAUGAGAGCCUGACCAGAGCCUCCUCCAAGCGUGAGGCCCUGGAGAAGACCAUGCGGAACAAGAUGGACAGUGAAAUGAGGAGGCUGCAAGACUUCAACCGGGAUCUUAGAGAGAGAUUGGAAUCUGCAAAUCGCCGCCUGGCAAGCAAGACACAGGAGGCCCAGGCCGGCAGUCAGGACAUGGUGGCCAAGCUGCUUGCUCAGAGCUACGAACAGCAGCAGGAGCAAGAGAAGCUGGAGCGAGAGAUGGCACUGCUGCGCGGCGCCAUCGAGGACCAGCGGCGGCGUGCCGAGCUGCUGGAGCAGGCUCUGGGCAAUGCGCAGGGCCGGGCAGCUCGAGCCGAAGAGGAGCUGCGCAAGAAGCAGGCCUAUGUGGAGAAAGUGGAGCGGCUGCAGCAGGCGCUCGGGCAGCUGCAGGCAGCCUGUGAGAAGCGGGAGCAGCUGGAGCUGCGUCUGCGGACUCGCCUGGAGCAGGAACUCAAGGCCCUGCGUGCACAGCAGAGACAGGCAGGUGCCCCAGGUGGUAGCAGUGGCAGUGGUGGGUCUCCAGAGCUCAGCGCCCUGCGACUGUCAGAACAACUGCGAGAGAAGGAGGAGCAGAUCCUGGCGCUGGAGGCCGACAUGACCAAGUGGGAGCAGAAGUAUUUGGAGGAACGUGCCAUGAGGCAGUUUGCCAUGGAUGCGGCUGCCACGGCUGCUGCUCAGCGUGACACCACUCUCAUCCGACAUUCCCCCCAGCCCUCACCCAGCAGCAGCUUCAAUGAGGGUCUGCUCACUGGUGGCCACAGGCAUCAGGAGAUGGAAAGCAGGUUAAAGGUGCUCCAUGCCCAGAUCCUGGAGAAGGAUGCAGUGAUCAAGGUCCUUCAGCAGCGCUCCAGGAGAGACCCUGGCAAGGCCAUCCAGGGCUCCCUGCGGCCUGCCAAGUCGGUGCCAUCUGUUUUCGCGGCUGCGGCAGCAGGAACCCAGGGCUGGCAAGGGCUCUCUUCUAGUGAGCGACAAACAGCAGACGCCCCUGCUCGGCUGACUACAGACAGAGCACCCACAGAGGAGCCAGUGGUCACAGCUCCCCCUGCUGCCCAUGCCAAACACGGGAGCAGAGAUGGGAGCACCCAGACUGAGGGCCCCCCAGACAGCACCUCCACCUGCCUGCCACCGGAGCCUGACAGCCUUCUGGGGUGCAGCAGUAGCCAGAGAGCAGCCUCUCUGGACUCUGUAGCUACAUCCAGAGUCCAGGACUUGUCAGACAUGGUGGAGAUACUGAUCUGAAGGAGGUGGUGCUUCAGGACUCUGAGCCAUUCUCUCCCCUCCUCUGCCCUGUGCCACUCUCAGCCAUUUCAGCAGCCCCGUCAACCGCUGCUCCGUCCCUUUCCCCAGCCAGACACUCAUUCCCAUUGACCAUCUGGUCCCAGGAGCUCAGGAGGAGGACCCCAGGGGAGAGGAGAGCUGUGAGAGCACCGGCACCCCCAGAAGACUCUGCUUCUUAGCCCACAUUCCUCCGGGCCUUAUGGAGAAUGAGGAUUCAGCCUUGACUUCUUGCCCAAGGCCUGCUACUGGGGUAGCAACUGACAGCUCAGAAAGGAGCUGAGCUCCCUCUGCCCUGCCAGUUGUCAGUCAGGCAGGGAGGGAGUGGCUGUGUUGGUUUGGGGAACUAAUUUCCACGGACGGCUGCCCGUGGACACCAGGUGGACUGGUUCACUAAUCAAGUCAGCCAUAUUGUUCUCUGGCUAAGUUUGGUUCCAGCCAACGUCAUCUGCUCUUCAGUUCCUCACUGCCUUCUUGGGAUACUAAGACUUGAAUUUUUUGGGGACUAUUAAGGGUGUUAGUCUUGGAGAAGACACAGCCUCACCUUCUCACUUGCUGUGGGUGAGGGGCCAUUUAAGUGGACUGGGAGACAGUGCGCAGUUUGUAUAUAAUUCCCUUUCUUGUGGAACAGAAGACUGAGGCCUGCAGGUUCCGAUGUGUCUCCAUGGGCUGUGCUCCCCUCUUCCUACUGUCAGUUUCUGAAACUUCUGACUGGCCUCCCAGUUAUGCCUCCUCCUCAAGUUCCUGGCCCGUGGAUGUUAAAGCUGCUCGAUUCCCAGGAUCUCGGCUGCCUUUUCCUCUAUCUUGAGCCCUAUAAAUGCCCACGGGACCCCCACCACCAGCCUCUUGAAGUGGCUCCACAGCUCCUGUCCCUGGAACAUCCUGUCAGUUUGGUCAUAAACCCUGAGCCAGAUGAAAUGAGCCACCGUGAACAGACAUCUGCCAUGCCCCCAGGUGGGCUUCGGUGGCCCUACCCGGUACCAGUUCUUUCUGAGAAACUGGAGAUGUCUUGUUAGCAUAAGUGUCUUCAUUCCCACCUGGAGGGUUUGGGAGAGGAGCAAAGCAGUUGAAAACUAGUUAAUGAGCUACAAGAGUCAAAUAGUCCUCUGAAUGGAGCCCCCAUCACAAAACAGUGCCCAGGAGGCUGGCUCCUCAAGCUACCCAUGCCCAGCGCCCUAAAGCAGCACCAGAUGCUUUGGAAUUGGGGUGAAACACCCACAUGGCAGCCUGCUAGCAGCAGUGACUUUGACUUCUGGUCUUAAAGAGUCCCUCACUUCAGCCCCAGGAGCUAUUGGUGGGUUUUAGCAGUUUUGUCUUUACCGUUUUUAGUUCUCCUUGAUUCUUUGUUUUCUUCCUUUAUCGUUUUUAGGUUUGGUAUGUGUUGUUUUAUUUCCAUGGUUCCUCAAGUUUCCUUUUUAAACAUUUGCAUUUGCUGGACAAUUGCAAUUUUUUUUAAAAAAUUCCCCUACCCCUGUUUAAAGCUGAAAAAUACAUUUGGUUCAUGUGCAUUGUUUACAAAGCAAAAAGAAAAAAGAGGAAAAAAAGGCAAAAAAUAUUGUGAAAGAAAAAAAACAACUUAAUAUAUUUUGGAUUAAUAUUUGGUAUUUCUUUUAAAGUAUUUUUUGUGCUGUGAACAUUUUCUGCCAAAGACCAUGAUGUGUGUCUGUAUGUUUAAGUUAUCGUAAAUAUUUAAAAUGUAAACAUGGCUGUUUUGUUAUGCCACCCUGUACCAGGAUUGCUGCCGCAUUCCACUGGGUAUAACAGUAUUUUAAUUAAAAAAAAAUAAUUAAAAGUGAUGUCUUUGCACAGGUGAGACUUUGCACUGAGGGAAGGGAAAGGGUGAGGAUUUUGGGGGGCCACCCAAGUCAUAGUCCAAUCUCUUCAAGGACCCAAGAUAGAAUUUAGGAAUUUUGUGAAGCUGCAUUAAGGAUAGAGUUGGAAUGAGGAUGUGGCUGGCAUUUUUCCCCUUUCAUAGAUAACAUUUCUUGAAGGCUGGGAGGGGAAGGAGGGCCUGGCAGAUGGCAGCCUCCCGAGGUAGGGCUGUGUUCUAAUCAGCUUUGUUCGGCCACACGCUGUGGUUAUCCACAGUGGGAGUGGGUGUCCAAAGAUGGCUUUAUCCUUCCCCCACUCCUUUUCCCACUCCCACCUAGCACAUAAAGUUUUGUCCGAAACCAUCCAGAAGGCCAGGCACCAUGCAGAGGACAUUCAAGAAUGUGCAUGUUCUUAGCCACCGCCUCCCUCCUUUGCUGUGACAUCACCACUCUUUCCUGAUGCUCAGGAAAGCAUAUUGCUCCAAUUCAAAAUUAAAGAAAGCCAUUCUCAGU